GCCUCCCUCCAGCGCCCAGCCUGGCUUCGCGGCGGAGGCGGCGCCUCUCCCGCAGGACGGAGCCAAGCUGGACUGCCGCGCCGCGCGGGGCGGGCAAAGGGGGCGCUGCGCUCGGCCCCGGGCAGGGAGUGACGGCGGCGGCGGCGGCUCCGGGCGAGCGUGGUCCCCGCGUGCGCACACGCACACGCCGCCGCGCAGGGACACACGGACCCCGGCCGCCAGCCGGCCACACAGGCGCGGAGACCCGGCUCGGCGCGCGCUCCUCGGCGCACACGCUCCCCAUCCCCGCGCCGCGCGGGCCGCGGACUUGCAGGCUGCGCGUCCUUUGCGGAGUCUGCCCCGGCCCCACGGACAGGCCCCGCAGUGAGCAGCCCAGAGACACAUUGGGGCUGACCUGCCGCUGCUGUCAGUGGGAGGCCAGUGGUGCUGGCCAAGAAGUGUCAUGGCUGGUGUCGUGCACGUUUCCCUGGCUGCUCUCCUCCUGCUGCCUAUGGCCCCUGCCAUGCAUUCUGACUGCAUCUUCAAGAAGGAGCAAGCCAUGUGCCUGGAGAAGAUCCAGAGGGCCAAUGAGCUGAUGGGCUUCAAUGAUUCCUCUCCAGGCUGUCCUGGGAUGUGGGACAACAUCACGUGUUGGAAGCCCGCCCAUGUGGGUGAGAUGGUCCUGGUCAGCUGCCCUGAGCUCUUCCGAAUCUUCAACCCAGACCAAGUCUGGGAGACCGAAACCAUUGGAGAGUCUGAUUUUGGUGACAGUAACUCCUUAGAUCUCUCAGACAUGGGAGUGGUGAGCCGGAACUGCACGGAGGAUGGCUGGUCGGAACCCUUCCCUCAUUACUUUGAUGCCUGUGGGUUUGAUGAAUAUGAAUCUGAGACUGGGGACCAGGAUUAUUACUACCUGUCAGUGAAGGCCCUCUACACGGUUGGCUACAGCACAUCCCUCGUCACCCUCACCACUGCCAUGGUCAUCCUUUGUCGCUUCCGGAAGCUGCACUGCACACGCAACUUCAUCCACAUGAACCUGUUUGUGUCGUUCAUGCUGAGGGCGAUCUCCGUCUUCAUCAAAGACUGGAUUCUGUAUGCGGAGCAGGACAGCAACCACUGCUUCAUCUCCACUGUGGAAUGUAAGGCCGUCAUGGUUUUCUUCCACUACUGUGUUGUGUCCAACUACUUCUGGCUGUUCAUCGAGGGCCUGUACCUCUUCACUCUGCUGGUGGAGACCUUCUUCCCUGAAAGGAGAUACUUCUACUGGUACACCAUCAUUGGCUGGGGGACCCCAACUGUGUGUGUGACAGUGUGGGCUACGCUGAGACUCUACUUUGAUGACACAGGCUGCUGGGAUAUGAAUGACAGCACAGCUCUGUGGUGGGUGAUCAAAGGCCCUGUGGUUGGCUCUAUCAUGGUUAACUUUGUGCUUUUUAUUGGCAUUAUCGUCAUCCUUGUGCAGAAACUUCAGUCUCCAGACAUGGGAGGCAAUGAGUCCAGCAUCUACUUAACAAAUUUAAGCCCGCGAGUCCCCAAGAAAGCCCGAGAGGACCCCCUGCCUGUGCCCUCAGACCAGCAUUCACUCCCUUUCCUGCGACUGGCCCGGUCCACCCUGCUGCUCAUCCCACUAUUCGGAAUCCACUACACAGUAUUUGCCUUCUCCCCAGAGAAUGUCAGCAAAAGGGAAAGACUCGUGUUUGAGCUGGGGCUGGGCUCCUUCCAGGGCUUUGUGGUGGCUGUUCUCUACUGUUUUCUGAAUGGUGAGGUACAAGCGGAGAUCAAGCGAAAAUGGCGAAGCUGGAAGGUGAACCGUUACUUCGCUGUGGACUUCAAGCACCGACACCCGUCUCUGGCCAGCAGUGGGGUGAAUGGGGGCACCCAGCUCUCCAUCCUGAGCAAGAGCAGCUCCCAAAUCCGCAUGUCUGGCCUCCCUGCUGACAAUCUGGCCACCUGAGCCAUGCUCCCCUCCUCCUCCUCUCCUCCAUCCACAGGCUGGGACCGCAGGCAGGUGCCAGCCCACGCAUGUUUGCGCCUCUUCCCUCCCCUUGGGCAGGCCCUGGGCUGGAAGCUUGGCUCCUGAGGGGGGAGAAGGAGGCAGGGCACAGACUGGAAUUGUCCCCUCCUUGUUUUGGUACUGGUCCCACCCACUGUGGUCCCCUGGGCCCUGACCCCAGACAUGUAAAUACUCCUCAAAUUUGGAAAAGUUGUCCCAUCCCUUCCCCCUUUGCCCCAGUGUCCCUGCUCACUUCCAGUCAGGUCUCAGCUCCACCCCACUGUUUCUUGGUCAGCCUCAGUGAUGGCCUGACCCCAGCUGUGAGGCCUUGUGAGCUAAGGCUGAAGAGACCUUGCCUGUGGGAGCUGGGGUGGUACCUGCCCCAACAGCCCCCCAUCAUCUGAUUUUGGGUGUGACCCCUCGAGUGUGCAUGCCACCCUGGGGCUCUUCUCAGUCCUGGGCCCAAGUCCCUGAAGCCUAGCAGAGGGCCAGCUCGGGUGGCCAGAACACCCCUUGGUGCAGGCCUCCUGGCACUCGCCUGGCAUCUUGGUGUCCGGGUGCUCAGCUCCUGGGUCCCAGGGCAGUGGGACAGCUCCCAGGCUCUUCUCAUCAGAGACUUCAGUUUGGGUGGGGAGUCUGCAGGUCAGGGAAGGUUCUGGUGCUUUUCGUUUGAUCCAAAAGGAGCUGAGAGCCAGAAAUGUGGCUGUGAUUGCGAAAGAGACGGAGUUUGGGAGACCCAUGGAAGAAAACCUUCGCCAUCUCCAUUGUUUUACCCCCAGCUCAAGAUGGACAGGGUUCUUCUGGUCAUCUCCCUUCCACCUCUUCCACCCUCAUGGAUGCCUUCCAGAAGCUGUCUCCAACCAUGCACACCACAGAGAGCCCUUAAGCCCUCCCCUCCCCAUUUCCCCUAAGUCAAAGCCAUGACUAGGAUGUACCAGCCACCUGCCUCUGAUGUCGGCGAAUCCUGAAGCACCUGCACCCGAAUCUGGGGCCCAGGGCUGCCCGACCCCCACUCCCAUGGAUGAUGAGGAGCCCCAGACACCAGCUCCUCUGGCCUGGACUCAACUAUUGAAAUCUCUCUGAGACCUCUGCAAAGAUGUCCCUUUUAUGCCCUUGACCUUGACUCACCAUGGGCUGCUGGGGUGUCGGGAGAAGCCACACCCAACAUGCCCAUUAGCAGAGGCUGCUGCUGAUGUGGCAGCUGCUCCCUACCACCCGCCCUGGCUCCCCAGCUGCAGGUUGCACACCCUCAGCCUGAGAAUGUAAAAUAGGGCAGUGCCCAGCUGGGGAGGUAGAGGAAAGUGCUAGAGUACAUGGUCCGUGUGUGGCCUAGCUCAUUCCAUGUCAGCAUUUGGUGUUACUCCUGUCCAAAUUCUGUUUGCAGACUUGUUUCAUGAUGAUGCUCUGGAAUGCUUGGGGACUUUGGGUGGAGGAGGAUGUUACUUCAUUUUAUAAAGAGGAAGGGGCCUGGGAGACUUGGGAAAAUGUUUCUGGAGAGGCUUUCAGAGUGGCUGGAAAAGGCUCUUGUUGCUGUAAUUUAGAGAGGAGCUCUGUGUCCUUGGCCAGUCAAGUAAGUUCCUGGAUCUUUGGCAAAGCCAGAGGAAGAAAGGAGCUACCUGCCCUUUCCUGGGCAUGCUUGGUGACUCAGAUUGAUCUUGGAGUGUGCAGUGGCCCUUCUACCCUGCACCUGACCUCAUGAUCCCCUCCACCUGCACUGGUGUGCAUUACUGAAGCAAGGGUCCUGUGGACAUCUUGCAUUUUGGGCACUGCUAGGGGGUCUGGGCUGCUUGGAAGGAGCCAUGGCCUAGGGUUCAGGGAACUAGACUCUAUCCCAGUUGGGUUCAGACUGCUGUGACUGUGGACACGAUGCUCCUUGUUCUGGGCUCCAGUUUUCCCAUUUGUGAGAUGAGGCAACUUCCAAUGCUUCUCUAGGCCCUGCACGUAAGUGAUUUUUCCAGUUCAAAGUCAAGACAGGUAAAAGGGCAUUCAUCAUUGUGCCUCAUAUCAGGUUUUGAUGAAUAUAUGUGUGUGUGUGUGUGUGUGUGUGUGUGUGUGUGUAGAGGGAUGGACAGGAUGCUGUUUAUUUUCCCUUUCUUGGAAAUGGACCUUCUGUCCCUUCCAUUUGGACACCACAGUGGAAGCUGGUGGCCUGGAAGGAAGGAUUAGGUCAUGGACAUUUGAACAGGUGCCUUGGGCAUGAUGUAUAGAUGCAGUCAUAUAUACCUUGCUGGGGUGGGGUGCCACCUCCAGUGGCCAGCUCCAGAUCCAAGGAGCAGCCCCCUGGGGAUGGACCCCAUUCAUUCAUCAUGACUCCCAACAGUUUUCAUUGUGGAAGAAGAAACUUUGGCAUUAUAGAGACAUCAUCACAAAACAGUAAAAACAAAAUCAACCCUGAACCCCAUGCACUGUGCUGCUUCCUGAGCCUGGCCCUGCAUCCUCAUAGAGGUGCCGGGUUCCUAUUGGUUAGUUGGUUGUUUUUCCGUCUGAGUGAAUUUUUGCCAGUCUUGUGAGCAGAUGUACCUGAUGUAUUCUCAAUGUUCCAAGAGGUUCUGGCCUUCAGGGUCACAGGCAGUAGGGGGACAGCAUAAGGUCUAUGUAAAACCCUUCCCUCUCUGACCCUCUGUUUUCAAAUCUGUAAAAUGGGCAAUAAGACUAGAUGAUUUGUAUAUAGCCCAAUGCAUCUCUGGAACUCUGUCUAAACACCAGCCAUCUACUUGGAAUGGGCCCCAGGACUGUGGUAUUUGCCUGGGCCAGGAAAGGAUAAGAAAUCCUGUCAUGUGAAGACAGCUUGAGAGGCUUGAGAAAAGUGGGGCUGGGGAGAAGCAGGCUUGUCAGACUCCACCCCUGUUGAUGAUCAUUCCUGGGAAGGGGUUUCUCGUUCUAUGCAAUCCUAAAGGACGAAACUCACCCAUGGGAGGCCGAAUUCUCCUUGGGAUGAAGAAAUUUCUCUUUCCCUGUCAUGAGUGUCCAGCCAGGGAGCAGGGAGGCAGUGUCAGGGAGGGACUCUCAUCCUGGAGGAAAUGGGAUUCCAAGUCAAGGAUGCUGAGGCUGUCAGGGAGCCAGAGAGGGGGGUCCAAGUGCGGGAUGUGGGUGGCUCUGUGGUUCAGUGGCUCUGUGGUAGUUCCUAGCACUGCAGACUUCAUGACUCCCCACUUAAGUCCAAGUCACAUUGUCUAUCCCAGUGUGUAGCUCUGUCACCCUGCUUGACACAUCCAGUGGCCUACAGCGACUCUUCUCUAACCCCACCCCCUCCAAGCUGGGUUCUUUGUGGAAGAAGGACAGGGAGCUAGAGCCAAGCCCUAGGCUUGAGAGACACCUGCAUCUAUAAUCCCCGCCAAGGAUGCCCACUCACCUCUCUCAUCUGAUCCUCACUCUUUGUGGAAGGGAAAGCUCAAAGGGACUCUCUCUCUCUCUCUCUUUUUUUUUUUUUUUGAGUAGUACCCUUGCCCUCUUCAUGGCCACUUCAAAGUGAAGCCAGCAAAGUGAUAAUACUUUAUCAUUUAGUAUUAUCAUAAAGUAUUAAUACUUUGUCAUAAAGUCCUCCUUGAGCCCAGGGACCAUGGAAGUCAGCUAGAAGAGCCCUGAGCAAGGAGCAAGGACUUGGGCUUCUCCACGCUUUGCUCCUGGCUUGUUUGACCUUGACUCAUUCCCCAUAUGUCUUUGAGGAGGCUCACAAAAUACUAAAGCUGGGAGGAAACUUGGAGAUCUAUAGGUCAAACCUCCCCAUUGGGCUGAUGAGAAAAUACACGCAGGCCUAGCAUGGUGCCUGCCACCAUGGUGGGAUCCAGUAUGUUUUAUAAAUCUGAAUGAGUAAAUGGCUCACCAAUUUAUGCAUAGCCCUGCACAUGAGCAGAAUGUGACACUCAAAGCAUCCAUGCAGUACGCAUGUAACCUUGCACAGGAGUGGGGCUCUGGUGACCGAAGGUUGUCCAGGACUCUUGCAGGAGAAGCAAUGGAGUCAGUGUGGUGUGGGGAGACCUACUUUUUAACCUGGGCUUAGCCACCUGCUCUGUGAUCCAGGGCUUACCUUCUUUGGGCCUCGGCCUCCUAAUCUGGGUAAUGGGGAGGACUUCAUUGGCAUUGUUAGUCCCACAGGCCAAGGAUAAGGUUGAAAUGAGACGGCUUGUGUGUGAAAAGAUUUUGGAAAUUACACAGAUGUGGGCUUGUUAUUGGGAUGAAGACUGCUGGAAGGGACUCCUUGCUGUUUAUCUACUGCUUUGAGCCCUCCUAAGUUAACCUGUGCCUCAUUUGUAAAACCACCAGCAUCAGGAGUAAGGGGGAGGCCAGAGGGCUCAGAUGGACACAGAAUUCUAGCUUUACCUGCAUCCGCUGAUUCAGUUUUCUGUUGGGAUCAGAGUGAGGAUACUUCCAUAUGGGUGAUAGCAGCCAUGCCCCUGGGAGUCAACUUCAAGGAUCUGGGACAUUUUGGUGUGCCCAUUCCUUCUUUUCCUGAACUCACAGUCUUGGGGUGUUUCUGCACUUGGCUAUGUGUGUCUUGUCUGAUGUCUGUCUUCUGUAGCUUUGCCUCUAUCAGGGCUGGAGUGGUGCAGCCCCUGGCAUCUCAGACAUGGUUCCUGCCUCACUUGUGGGAGCUGGACCAGCCUGGGUUUCAUCUCCCACAGUAAAGCUAAGUAAGCCCCACAGACCUUACUGCUACUGCUGCUGCCAUUAAUGCUGUGCUCACUAUCUUGUCCAGGAUUUUAAGGAUGUCAGACUGCUGUAGAUGACUCAAUAAAUGUUUUGCCAUUUUU